GCUCGGAGCUGUAGCCGCCGCUGCCGCCGCUGCUCUUGGCUCGGGGACGCGGGCGGGCGCUCCGAGAGGCUCUGGUGCCUGCGGCUGCUGCUCUCCUCCGGCGCCCGGGGCUGCGGCGCUCCGGGUCCCGGCCCCUGUCCCGGCAUCUCUCGGGUCCCUGAGCCCCGGCCCCGGGUCCCGCGUCCGGCCGGAGAGAACGCACUCAGCUGCUCGAGCCGCCCCGGGCUCGCGCCCCCGGGCCAUGAAGAGGGGCCCGUGAGGCGCGCGCGGAGUCGGAGGAAGAGGAGGGAGGAGGGAGGCCGAGGAGGAGGGCGCGGGAGGCGGAGGAUGCCGCCGCGGCUGCUGCCGCCGCCGCCACCCGCGGGUCCCCGGCGACCCUGACUCCAGACCCGAGGAUGGAGCCGGCGCUGGGCGCUGCAGCUGCUCCCGGCGCGUCCCCGACCAGGUAGCUGGUGUCACUUCGGUGUGGUUGGAAGAAGACUUUCUCCCCAGCUGCAUUCCCGGAGGCGCCCUUUCGACCUGGAGGCCGGGUCUGCUGGCCACAGGGCUGCCGCACUGGCUGGGACUGCCAGCUGGGCCUGGAGACGCUGGUGGCUGUGGACUCCCCAGCUUGGAGCAGUCCCUCUUUGACCUCACCCCUUGGAGAAGCAGCCCCAUGAAGGUGCCCAGCCAUGCAAUGUUCCUGGAAGGCCGUCCUCCUCCUUGCCCUGGCCUCCAUUGCCAUCCAGUACACGGCCAUCCGCACCUUCACCGCCAAGUCCUUUCACACCUGCCCCGGGCUGGCAGAGGCCGGGCUGGCCGAGCGACUGUGCGAGGAGAGCCCCACCUUCGCCUACAACCUCUCCCGCAAGACCCACAUCCUCAUCCUGGCCACCACGCGCAGUGGCUCCUCCUUCGUGGGCCAGCUCUUCAACCAGCACCUGGACGUCUUCUACCUGUUUGAGCCCCUCUACCACGUCCAGAACACGCUCAUCCCCCGCUUCACCCAGGGCAAGAGCCCGGCCGACCGGCGGGUCAUGCUAGGCGCCAGCCGCGACCUCCUGCGGAGCCUCUACGACUGCGACCUCUACUUCCUGGAGAACUACAUCAAGCCGCCGCCGGUCAACCACACCACCGACAGGAUCUUCCGCCGCGGGGCCAGCCGGGUCCUCUGCUCCCGGCCUGUGUGCGACCCUCCGGGGCCAGCCGACCUGGUCCUGGAGGAGGGGGACUGUGUGCGCAAGUGCGGGCUACUCAACCUGACCGUGGCGGCCGAGGCGUGCCGCGAGCGCAGCCACGUGGCCAUCAAGACGGUGCGCGUGCCCGAGGUGAACGACCUGCGCGCCCUGGUGGAAGACCCGCGAUUAAACCUCAAGGUCAUCCAGCUGGUCCGAGACCCCCGCGGCAUUCUGGCUUCGCGCAGCGAGACCUUCCGCGACACGUACCGGCUCUGGCGGCUCUGGUACGGCACCGGGAGGAAACCCUACAACCUGGACGUGACGCAGCUGACCACGGUGUGCGAGGACUUCUCCAACUCCGUGUCCACCGGCCUCAUGCGGCCCCCGUGGCUCAAGGGCAAGUACAUGUUGGUGCGCUACGAGGACCUGGCUCGGAACCCUAUGAAGAAGACCGAGGAGAUCUACGGGUUCCUGGGCAUCCCGCUGGACAGCCACGUGGCCCGCUGGAUCCAGAACAACACGCGGGGCGACCCCACCCUGGGCAAGCACAAAUACGGCACCGUGCGAAACUCGGCGGCCACGGCCGAGAAGUGGCGCUUCCGCCUCUCCUACGACAUCGUGGCCUUUGCCCAGAACGCCUGCCAGCAGGUGCUGGCCCAGCUGGGCUACAAGAUCGCCGCCUCGGAGGAGGAGCUGAAGAACCCCUCGGUCAGCCUGGUGGAGGAGCGGGACUUCCGCCCCUUCUCGUGACCCGGGCGGUGCGGGUGGGGGCGGGAGGCGCAAGGUGUCGGUUUUGAUAAAAUGGACCGUUUUUAACUGUUGCCUUAUUAACCCCUCCCUCUCCCACCUCAUCUUCGUGUCCUUCCUGCCCCCAGCUCACCCCACUCCCUUCUGCCCCUUUUUUGUCUCUGAAAUUUGCACUACGUCUUGGACGGGAAUCACUGGGGCAGAGGGCGCCUGAAGUAGGGUCCCGCCCCCCCCCCCCCCAUUCAGACACAUGGAUGUUGGGUCUCUGUGCGGACGGUGACAAUGUUUACAAGCACCACAUUUACACAUCCACACACGCACACGGGCACUCGCGAGGCGACUUCUCAAGCUUUUGAAUGGGUGAGUGGUCGGGUAUCUAGUUUUUGCACUGUCUUACUAUUCAAGGUAAGAGGAUACAAACAAGAGGACCACUUGUCUCUAAUUUAUGAAUGGUGUCCAUCCUUUCCCCAUCCCUGCCUCCUGCCCCUGACGCCCAUUUCCCCCCUUAGAGCAGCGAAACUGCCCCCUCCUGCCCGCCCUUGCCUGUCGGUGAGGCAGGUUUUUACUGUGAGGUGAACGUGGACCUGUUUCUGUUUCCAGUCUGUGGUGAUGCUGUCUGUCUGUCUGAGUCUCGUGGCCGCCCCUGGACCAGUGAUGACUGAUGAAUCUUAUGAGCUUCUGAUUGAUCUCGGGGUCCAUCUGUGAUAUUUCUUUGUGCCAAAAAGAAAAAAAAAGAGUGGAUCAGUUUGCUAAAUGAACAUUGAAAUUGAAAUGCUUUAUCUGUGUUUUCUGUAAAUAAAAGAGUGCAAUAAUCUCUGUGUGUGAUUGCAGGACAUUCUGAAUGGGUACGAGAGGGCCUCAGCCGGGUCUGGGUGUUCCUAGCUUUGGGGAGGACAGCGAGAGAGAGGUGGAGGUGGGAAUUAAAUGACAAGUCUGCCUUUCAGAACUCUUGUCACCCUCAACACUGAGUUUAGUUUAGGUUUUUGUUUUGUUUUGUUUUGAGACAGAGUCUCGCUCUGUCACCCAGGCUGGAGUGCAAUGGCGCCAUCUCGGCUCACUGCAACCUCUGCCUCCCAGGUUCAAGCAGUUCUCCCGCCUCAGCCUCCCGAGUGACUGGGACUACAGGUGCACACUGCCACACCUGGCUAUUUUUUUUUUUUUUUGGAUUUUAGUAGAGACGGGGUUUCACCGUGUUGUCCAGGCUGGUCGCGAACUCCUGAGCUCUGGGCAUUCCUCCUGCCUCAGCCUCCCAAAGUGCUGGGAUUGCAGACUUGAGCCACCUCACCCAGCCGUUUUUUUUUUCCUUCAGUCAGUUGAGACCGGGUAACUUAUAGCCAGGGAUAAUGUUCAAAGUCUUUAACAAGUGGUAUGGCUUGCUGAAUCAGAGUAGCUGGAGGUAAGAAUGACAUCCUGGAAUCCCUUCUUGUGCUAAAUGUUACCCAUUUAGUUGGUGGGUCUGGGUCUAGGAUAGCCAGGGAGGGGGAAACUUCAAGGGGUGGGGUGCCUCAGGGCAGUGGCUGCUGACCCACAGACCUGGAAGUAUUUGACUAUUUGAAUAACUGGUACAGGUUUACUGGUGUCUACACUGGCAGAGAAUCUGCUGUGCUUCCUCCCCUUCCCUUCGUGGCAAUCUAGCAGGUUGCUCCAGGCAGCUUCCCCAGCUCUUAUUCCAAGAAAACCUGCCCCUGGGGUGGCUGCAGGUCACAGCUUUGUUGUCCUGGGACAAAGGAGUGUCUGGUGAUUAGGCAGCCCCAGGGGUCCUAGCCAACUGGAAGAAGGGCUUCCUGAGGAAACACAGUCCUGGGCUAUUUUAUAUGUGUCAGGAGGAUGUAGACAGUUCAACAGCUCUAGCAAAUGCCUUAACUAAUAGUGGCUUAAUCAAGAUAGGUGAUUUUCUUUUGUAAAAAAUUUUACUGGGGUAAAAUAACAGAAUGUAAAAUUUACCAUCUUAACCUUUUUAAGGUGUACCAUUCAUUAAAUACAUUCACAACGUGUGCCACCA